CUCCGCCGCAGCCGCCUCAGAGCGGCAGGAGGGAGCAGUCGGUCGCUGCGCCCCGGCGGGCCACUUUCCCGGGACCCCGCUCGUCUUCCUUGGGCCGAGAUUUUCCACUGCGCCCCUCCGAGUACCCGGGUUCCAAACCCCUAGCCACGACAUGGAAGAAUUUUUGCAACGCGCCAAAUCUAAACUGAAUCGAAGCAAACGCUUGGAGAAGGUCCAUGUGGUUAUUGGGCCUAAAUCGUGUGACUUGGAUUCUCUCAUUUCUACCUUCACAUAUGCUUACUUUCUAGACAAGGUCAGUCCACCAGGGGUUCUGUGUUUACCAGUGCUGAACAUACCAAGAACUGAAUUCAACUACUUCACCGAGACGAGGUUUAUUUUAGAAGAGCUAAAUAUUUCCGAAUCAUUCCACAUAUUCCGGGAUGAAAUUAACCUGCAUCAGCUAAAUGAUGAAGGGAAGUUAUCGAUAACACUUGUUGGCAGCAGUGUGCUGGCGAGUGAAGACAAAACUUUAGAAUCAGCAGUUGUCAAAGUCAUUAAUCCGGUUGAGCAGAGCGAUGCCAACGUUGAGUUCCGAGAGUCUUCCUCUUCUCUCGUGCUAAAGGAGAUUCUCCAAGAGGCUCCUGAGCUCAUCACCGAGCAACUGGCUCAUCGCCUCAGAGGUAGCAUUCUUUUCAAGUGGAUGACCAUGGAAUCAGAGAAGAUCUCAGAGAAGCAGGAGGAAAUUCUUUCUAUCCUGGAAGAAAAAUUUCCUAACUUGCCUCCAAGAGAGGACAUCAUCAACGUCCUACAGGAGACCCAGUUCAGUGCUCAGGGUUUAAGUAUUGAACAGACAAUGUUGAAAGAUCUAAAGGAGCUGUCAGAUGGAGAAAUAAAAGUGGCCAUUAGUACUGUGAGCAUGAACCUUGAGAAUUGUCUAUUUCACAGCAAUAUUACCAGUGACUUGAAAGCAUUUACAGACAAGUUUGGUUUUGAUGUCCUCAUCCUGUUCUCCAGCUAUCUGUCAGAGGAGCAGCAGCCGAGACGACAGAUUGCUGUGUACUCAGAAAACAUGGAGCUGUGCAGUCAGAUUUGCUGUGAGCUGGAAGAGUGUCAGAACCCUUGCCUAGAACUGGAGCCCUUUGACUGUGGCUGUGAUGAGAUCCUGGUGUACCAACAAGAGGACCCUUCAGUGACUUGUGAUCAGGUGGUUCUCGUUGUCAAGGAAGUCAUCAACAGGAGGUGUCCAGAGAUGGUCUCCAAUAGCCGGACAUCCUCAACAGAAGCCGUGGCAGGCAGUGCCCCCCUCUCCCAGGGGUCUUCUGGGAUUAUGGAAUUGUAUGGUUCUGACAUAGAGCCACAACCCAGCUCUGUGAAUUUCAUAGAGAACCCUCCAGAUCUCAAUGAUUCUAACCAGGCUCAGGUGGAUGCCAAUGUAGACCUUGUUAGCCCAGACAGCGGACUGGCUACCAUUAGGAGCAGCCGCUCAUCCAAGGAGAGCUCUGUUUUCCUCAGUGACGACAGCCCCGUGGGAGAAGGUGCUGGGCCUCACCACACCCUUCUCCCAGGGCUUGACUCCUACAGCCCCAUCCCUGAAGGGGCGGUGGCGGAGGAACAUGCAUGGUCUGGAGAACACGGUGAGCACUUCGACCUCUUCAAUUUUGACCCAGCACCCAUGGCUUCUGGGCAGUCCCAGCAAUCUUCUCAUUCUGCAGACUACUCCCCAGCAGAUGACUUCUUCCCCAACAGUGACCUGUCAGAAGGACAGCUCCCCGCUGGGCCUGAAGGACUUGAUGGCAUGGGAACCAACAUGUCUAAUUAUUCAUCCAGUUCACUUUUGUCAGGGGCUGGCAAAGAUAGCCUUGUGGAACAUGAUGAGGAGUUUGUCCAGAGACAAGACAGUCCCAGAGAUAACUCUGAAAGAAAUUUGAGCCUGACAGAUUUUGUGGGAGAUGAAUCCCCUUCCCCAGAAAGGCUAAAAAAUACUGGAAAGAGGAUCCCACCAACACCCAUGAAUAGUUUAGUAGAAAGCUCGCCAUCCACUGAAGAACCAGCCUCACUCUAUACAGAAGAUAUGACCCAAAAAGCAACUGACACAGGUCACAUGGGGCCACCUCAGACCCAUGCACGGUGCAGCAGCUGGUGGGGUGGUUUGGAAAUUGACUCCAAAAAUAUUGCAGAUGCGUGGAGUUCCAGUGAACAGGAAUCUGUUUUCCAGAGCCCUGAAUCAUGGAAAGAGCAUAAGCCAAGCUCCAUUGAUAGGAGAGCCUCAGAUUCUGUAUUUCAACCAAAGAGCCUCGAAUUUACAAAGUCAGGUCCCUGGGAGUCUGAAUUUGGUCAGCCUGAACUGGGUAGCAAUGAUAUUCAAGACAAAAAUGAGGAAAGCUUGCCGUUCCAGAACCUGCCCAUGGAGAAGUCACCUUUGCCAAAUACAUCUCCCCAAGGAACAAACCACCUGAUAGAAGACUUUGCUUCUUUGUGGCAUUCUGGUCGCUCUCCCACAGCCAUGCCCGAGCCCUGGGGAAAUCCUACAGAUGAUGGUGAACCAGCAGCUGUGGCGCCAUUCCCAGCCUGGAGUGCAUUUGGUAAAGAAGAUCAUGAUGAAGCUUUAAAAAAUACCUGGAAUUUGCACCCAACAAGCAGCAAGACACCUUCUGUUAGGGACCCGAAUGAGUGGGCCAUGGCAAAAAGUGGGUUUGCCUUUUCUUCUUCAGAACUACUGGACAAUUCACCCAGUGAGAUAAACAAUGAAGCAGCUCCAGAAAUCUGGGGCAAGAAAAACAAUGACUCCAGGGAUCACAUCUUUGCACCUGGAAAUCCCAGUUCUGAUCUGGAUCACACAUGGACUAAUUCUAAGCCACCAAAAGAAGAUCAGAAUGGUUUAGUGGAUCCUAAAACUAGGGGCAAGGUAUAUGAAAAGGUAGAUUCCUGGAACCUUUUUGAGGAGAAUAUGAAGAAAGGAGGGUCAGAUGUCCUAGUUCCUUGGGAAGAUUCCUUCUUAUCUUACAAAUGUUCUGAUUACAGUGCAUCCAACCUAGGAGAAGAUUCGGUGCCUUCCCCCUUAGAUACCAAUUAUUCCACCUCAGACUCUUACACAUCACCAACAUUUGCUGGAGACGAAAAGGAAACUGAACACAAGCCAUUUGCUAAAGAGGAAGGUUUUGAGUCAAAAGAUGGUAACUCCACGGCAGAGGAGACUGACAUUCCUCCUCAGUCACUGCAACAGUCAUCUCGAAAUCGAAUCAGUUCAGGUCCUGGGAACCUAGACAUGUGGGCUUCACCUCAUACAGAUAACAGUUCUGAAAUAAAUACCACUCACAACCUGGAUGAAAAUGAACUCAAGACAGAGCACACAGAUGGUAAGAAUAUCUCCAUGGAGGAUGACGUCGGGGAAAGCAGCCAGUCCAGUUACGACGACCCCAGCAUGAUGCAACUGUACAAUGAAACAAACCGACAACUCACACUUUUGCACAGCAGCACCAACUCCCGGCAGACGGCCCCUGACAGUCUCGACUUGUGGAACAGAGUGAUUUUGGAGGAUACUCAGUCCACUGCAACGAUCUCAGAUAUGGACAAUGAUUUGGACUGGGAUGACUGCAGUGGGGGUGCGGCAAUCCCCAGUGAUGGUCAAACAGAAGGAUACAUGGCUGAAGGUUCCGAGCCGGAAACCCGAUUUACAGUGAGACAGCUGGAACCCUGGGGCUUGGAGUAUCAGGAAGCAAAUCAGGUAGAUUGGGAGCUCCCUGCCUCUGAUGAGCAUACCAAGGACAGUGCUCCCAGUGAACAUCACACAUUGAAUGAGAAAAGUGGGCAGCUAAUUGCAAACAGUAUUUGGGAUUCUGUCAUGAGAGAUAAAGACAUGUCAUCAUUCAUGUUACCAGGCUCCUCACAUAUCACAGAUUCAGAGCAAAGGGAAUUGCCUCCUGAAAUCCCCAGCCAUUCAGCAAAUGUUAAAGACACUCAUUCCCCAGAUGCGCCAGCAGCCUCUGGAACCAGUGAAUCAGAGGCACUUAUAUCUCAUCUUGACAAGCAGGACACAGAGAGGGAAACCCUGCAAAGUGAUGCAGCAUCCUUGGCGACUAGGCUUGAGAAUCCAGGGUAUUUUCCACACCCAGAUCCAUGGAAAGGUCAUGGCGAUGGACAAAGUGAAAGUGAGAAGGAAGCCCAGGGAGCCACUGACAGGGGGCACCUUGAUGAAGAGGAGGUGAUCGCCUCUGGUGUGGAGAAUGCCUCAGGGAUUUCUGAAAAAGGGCAGAGUGACCAGGAACUGUCUUCUCUGGUUGCAUCUGAACAUCAGGAAAUCUGCAUUAAAUCAGGCAAAAUCAGCUCUCUUGCUGUCACUUUCAGUCCUCAAACCGAGGAACCAGAGGAAGUUUUAGAGUAUGAGGAGGGGUCUUACAAUCUAGACUCCCGUGAUGUGCAAACAGGGAUGUCCGCAGAUAACCUGCAGCCAAAAGAUACCCAUGAAAAACACCUCAUGAGUCAAAGAAAUUCAGGUGAAACUACUGAGACUUCAGAUGGGAUGAAUUUCACAAAAUAUGUAUCUGUACCUGAAAAGGAUCUUGAGAAAACUGAAGAAUGUAACUUUCUAGAGCCAGAGAACGUGGGUGGAGGGCCACCUCACAGAGUUCCCCGAAGUCUUGAUUUUGGGGACGUCCCUAUAGACAGUGAUGUGCAUGUCAGCAGCACAUGUUCUGAGAUAACCAAAAAUCUUGACGUUAAGGGGUCUGAAAAUAGCCUUCCAGGAGCCGGUUCGUCUGGAAAUUUUGACAGAGAUACUAUUUCUAGUGAGUAUACUCAUUCAAGUGCAUCAAGUCCUGAGUUAAAUGACUCUUCAGUUGCACUGUCCUCCUGGGGCCAGCAACCCAGUUCUGGGUAUCAAGAAGAAAACCAAGGCAACUGGAGUGAACAGAAUCACCAAGAAUCUGAACUAAUUACCACUGAUGGCCAAGUAGAAAUAGUUACCAAAGUGAAGGAUUUAGAGAAAAACAGAAUAAAUGAGUUUGAAAAGAGCUUUGAUCGCAAAACUCCUACAUUUUUAGAGAUCUGGAAUGACUCAGUUGAUGGUGAUUCCUUUUCCUCUUUAUCCAGUCCUGAAACAGGCAAAUAUUCUGAACAUUCAGGGACACAUCAGGAAAGCAAUCUAAUUGCUAGCUACCAGGAGAAAAAUGAACAUGACAUUUCUGCAACUGUGCAGCCAGAGGAUGCCAGGGUCAUUUCAACAAGCUCAGGUUCUGAUGAUGACAGUGUCGGUGGUGAAGAGUCAAUAGAGGAAGAGAUCCAGGUGGCCAACUGCCACGUUGCUGAGGAUGAAUCCAGAGCUUGGGAUUCAUUGAAUGAAUCUAAUAAGUUCUUGGUCACAGCUGAUCCUAAGUCUGAAAAUAUUUAUGACUACCUAGACAGCUCAGAGCCAGCAGAGAAUGAGAAUAAGUCAAACCCAUUCUGUGACAAUCAACAAAGCAGCCCUGAUCCCUGGACUUUCUCACCAUUAACGGAGACUGAAAUGCAGAUUACAGCAGUGGAGAAGGAGAAGAGAUCUUCUCCAGAAACAGGGACAACAGGAGAUGUUGCAUGGCAAAUAUCUCCCAAAGCUUCGUUCCCAAAGAACGAAGAUAAUUCUCAACUGGAAAUGCUGGGCUUCUCAGCUGAUAGCACUGAGUGGUGGAAGGCCUCACCCCAGGAAGGGAGACUAAUUGAAAGUCCAUUUGAAAGGGAGCUGUCUGACUCCAGUGGUGUGUUGGAGAUAAAUUCUUCAGUACACCAAAAUGCCAGUCCCUGGGGAGUACCAGUUCAGGGUGAUAUUGAGCCCGUGGAAACACACUAUACUAAUCCUUUUAGUGACAACCAUCAGUCACCCUUUCUGGAAGGUAAUGGGAAGAACUCCCAUGAGCAACUCUGGAACAUUCAACCAAGGCAGCCAGACCCAGAUGCUGACAAGUUCAGCCAGCUUGUAAAAUUAGACCAAAUUAAAGAAAAGGACUCAAGAGAGCAAACCUUUGUGUCUGCUGCUGGUGAUGAGCUGACUCCUGAAACACCUACCCAAGAGCAGUGUCAGGACACCAUGCUGCCAGUCUGUGAUCAUCCGGACACAGCCUUUACUCACGCAGAGGAAAAUAGUUGUGUUACAUCUAAUGUUUCAACUAAUGAAGGUCAAGAAACAAAUCAGUGGGAACAAGAAAAAUCAUACCUAGGUGAGAUGACAAAUUCAAGCAUUGCCACAGAAAAUUUUCCUGCUGUCAGUUCUCCCACCCAACUGAUAAUGAAGCCAGGCUCUGAAUGGGAUGGCUCUACCCCAAGUGAGGACUCCCGAGGUACCUUUGUGCCAGAUAUUUUACAUGGCAACUUUCAAGAGGGUGGGCAGCUGGCCUCUGCCGCGCCUGACUUGUGGAUAGAUGCUAAGAAGCCCUUCAGUUUGAAAGCAGAUGGUGAGAAUCCUGAUAUCCUGACGCACUGCGAACAUGACAGCAAUUCUCAGGCUUCCGACAGCCCUGAUAUAUGUCACGAUUCUGAAGCAAAGCAAGAGACUGAGAAGCACCUCAGUGCUUGCAUGGGACCUGAAGUGGAAUCCAGUGAGCUUUGUCUCACUGAGCCAGAGAUAGAUGAAGAACCCAUUUAUGAGCCUGGACGGGAGUUUGUCCCAUCCAAUGCAGAACUCGAUUCUGAAAACGCAACUGUGCUGCCUCCAAUUGGCUAUCAAGCAGACAUAAAGGGCUCCUCUCAGCCCGCCUCUCAUAAAGGUUCACCUGAACCUUCUGAAAUAAACGGUGACAACAGUACAGGUUUACAAGUAUCAGAAAAAGGAGCCAGCCCAGAUAUGGCACCAAUUUUGGAACCAGUUGACAGAAGAAUCCCAAGGAUUGAAAAUGUGGCAACUAGCAUUUUUGUAACUCACCAAGAGCCAACUCCAGAAGGUGACGGUUCUUGGAUAUCAGACAGCUUUUCUCCUGAAAGUCAGCCUGGUGCAAGAGCUUUGUUUGAUGGUGAUCCACAUUUAUCCACAGAGAAUCCUGCCUUGGUUCCUGAUGCUUUGCUAGCCUCAGACACUUGUCUGGAUAUAAGCGAAGCUGCCUUUGACCACAGUUUCAGCGAUGCCUCAGGUCUCAACACAUCCACGGGAACAAUAGAUGACAUGAGUAAACUGACAUUAUCCGAAGGCCAUCCGGAAACGCCAGUUGAUGGGGACCUAGGGAAGCAAGAUAUCUGCUCAUCUGAAGCCUCGUGGGGUGAUUUUGAAUAUGAUGUAAUGGGCCAGAAUAUCGAUGAAGAUUUACUGAGAGAGCCUGAACACUUCCUGUAUGGUGGUGACCCUCCUUUGGAGGAAGAUUCUCUGAAGCAGUCGCUGGCACCGUACACACCUCCCUUUGAUUUGUCUUAUCUCACAGAACCUGCCCAGAGUGCUGAAACAAUAGAGGAAGCUGGGUCUCCAGAGGAUGAAUCUCUGGGAUGCAGAGCAGCAGAGAUAGUGCUUUCUGCACUUCCUGAUCGAAGAAGUGAGGGAAACCAGGCUGAGACCAAAAACAGACUGCCUGGAUCCCAGCUGGCUGUGCUGCAUAUUCGUGAAGACCCUGAGUCCGUUUAUUUGCCGGUAGGAGCAGGCUCCAACAUUUUGUCUCCAUCAAACGUUGACUGGGAAGUAGAAACAGAUAAUUCUGAUUUACCAGCAGGUGGAGACAUAGGACCACCAAAUGGUGCCAGCAAGGAAAUAUCAGAAUUGGAAGAAGAAAAAACAAUUCCUACCAAAGAGCCUGAGCAGAUAAAAUCAGAAUACAAGGAAGAAAGAUGUACAGAGAAGAAUGAAGAUCGUCAUGCACUACACAUGGAUUACAUACUUGUAAACCGUGAAGAAAAUUCACACUCAAAGCCAGAGACCUGUGAAGAAAGAGAAAGCAUAGCUGAAUUAGAAUUGUAUGUAGGUUCCAAAGAAACAGGGCUGCAGGGAACUCAGUUAGCAAGCUUCCCAGACACAUGUCAGCCAGCCUCCUUAAAUGAAAGAAAAGGUCUCUCUGCAGAGAAAAUGUCUUCUAAAAGCGAUACGAGAUCAUCUUUUGAAAGCCCUGCACAAGACCAGAGUUGGAUGUUCUUGGGCCAUAGUGAGGUUGGUGAUCCAUCACUGGAUGCCAGGGACUCAGGGCCUGGGUGGUCUGGCAAGACUGUGGAGCCGUUCUCUGAACUCGGCUUGGGUGAGGGUCCCCAGCUGCAGAUUCUGGAAGAAAUGAAGCCUCUAGAAUCUUUGGCACUAGAGGAAGCCUCUGGUCCAGUCAGCCAAUCACAGAAGAGUAAGAGCCGAGGCAGGGCUGGCCCGGAUGCAGUUACGUUGCAGGCUGUCACCCAUGACAAUGAAUGGGAAAUGCUUUCACCACAGCCUGUUCAGAAAAACAUGAUCCCUGACACGGAAAUGGAGGAGGAGACAGAGUUCCUUGAGCUCGGAACCAGGAUAUCAAGACCAAAUGGACUACUGUCAGAGGAUGUAGGAAUGGACAUCCCCUUUGAAGAGGGCGUGCUGAGUCCCAGUGCUGCAGACAUGAGGCCUGAACCUCCUAAUUCUCUGGAUCUUAAUGACACUCAUCCUCGGAGAAUCAAGCUCACAGCCCCAAAUAUCAAUCUUUCUCUGGACCAAAGUGAAGGAUCUAUUCUCUCUGAUGAUAACUUGGACAGUCCAGAUGAAAUUGACAUCAAUGUGGAUGAACUUGAUACCCCCGAUGAAGCAGAUUCUUUUGAGUACACUGGCCAUGAAGAUCCCACAGCCAACAAAGAUUCUGGCCAAGAGUCAGAGUCUAUUCCAGAAUAUACGGCCGAAGAGGAACGGGAGGACAACCGGCUUUGGAGGACAGUGGUCAUUGGAGAACAAGAGCAGCGCAUUGACAUGAAGGUCAUCGAGCCCUACAGGAGAGUCAUUUCUCACGGAGGAGAUUCAGGAUACUAUGGGGACGGUCUAAAUGCCAUCAUUGUGUUUGCCGCCUGUUUUCUGCCAGACAGCAGUCGGGCGGAUUACCACUAUGUCAUGGAAAAUCUUUUCCUAUAUGUAAUAAGUACUUUAGAGUUGAUGGUAGCUGAAGACUAUAUGAUUGUGUACUUGAAUGGUGCAACCCCAAGAAGGAGGAUGCCAGGGCUAGGCUGGAUGAAGAAAUGCUACCAGAUGAUUGACAGACGGUUGAGGAAGAAUUUGAAAUCAUUCAUCAUUGUUCAUCCAUCUUGGUUCAUCAGAACAAUCCUUGCUGUGACACGACCUUUUAUAAGUUCAAAAUUCAGCAGUAAAAUUAAAUAUGUCAAUAGCUUAUCAGAACUCAGUGGGCUGAUCCCAAUGGAUUGCAUCCACAUUCCAGAGAGCAUCAUCAAGUACGAUGAAGAGAGAUCUUAUAAGAGAAGUGUGAGACUGGAUGAAGAACUGAGGGAAGCAUCAGAGGCAGCUAAGUAAGACUUGGUUUUCGUUUAGCGGCUGGCAUGAUGUUGGCUUGCAUUUCAGAACUGAAUUGGGAAAAUCUGCAUGCCUGGUGUUUUAUUCCUGCUUCCUGAUAAUAAUGCACUUUAGAAAUUCUCUUUCUCCUAUGAUAGAUGUAAUCUCUAUUAUUCUUACUACAAUCUAUUUUUCCCCAUGAUCUUGCUUAUACUGAGGAAUGUAUUUGUCACUGUUGUUGUUGUUUUUUAAUGUACACGCAAUUCUAGGCACCACAACAAAAGAGCACAUCACAGGCACUGCCACAUAUAGUGUGACAUCGAGAUGAUCAUUAGGUAUUGAGGCAACAGAACCUCACUAAUUCAUACCAGUGGGGAGGAAUAAUAACACAUCGAGAUUUGGAAGAUUUUUGUAGAAUCAAUUUCACGGCCUUCUAUGAAUUAAAACAACAACUUACUUAAUGACUUUGGAAAUAUUGCUUAACUAACAGCCUUUGAGCUAUUUUGAUGAAUAGAAAAACAAAAGUCAUUGCCCACUAUUGCUAAAGUAUGAAUCUCAAAAAGGCAAAAUUACAACUCUCAUGCAAAUAUAAAAUGAACACAUGCCAAUGAUUUUAUUCAACUAAUUAUUUAAUGCAGGAACCACUAAGGUGUUAAAGCCAGUUCAAAGAACAUUUGAGCAGCUAGAUAUCUAUAGGCAAUUUAUAGAAGAAUAUUUGGAUAAGAUUGUUGGGUUAGAUACAAAACUGGUUAAUAAACAACAGGGCAAUAAACUGUAAUAUUGAGGUUGUCUUUUCCACUGGACAGAAAUUAUUUGCAUCUCUGCUGGACAGAAACUACAAGUUAACCUCUGCCCCUAUUGAGCUGUAAAAUAGCCCAACCAAUAGAAAGUCAGACCCCUGUAAUCCCAGCACUUUGGGAGGCCGAGAUGGGUGGAUCACGAGGUCAGGAGAUCGAGACCAUCCUGGCCAACAUGGUGAAACCCCGUCUCUACUAAAAAUACAAAAAUUAGCUGGGCAUGGUGGUGCACGCCUAUAGUCCGAGCUACUCGGGAGGCUGAGGAAGGAGAAUCGUUUGAACCUGGGAGGCGGAGAUUGCAGUGAGCCGAGAUCAUGCCACUGCACUCCAGCCUGGGGACAGAGCGAGACUCCAUCUCAAAAAAAAAAAAAAAUCCAGUCAUUCUCUUUUCUCGUUUCCAAGUUACAAAGAAAUUUUCUGAUAAUACAUGUUAGAUAUAACCAAGUACUAUUUGAAAAGUUUGCUGAAUUAAGCACAUUAAGUUUCUUCCCUAUUUUAAAUGUUGCUUAUGCUGUUAAUUUUUAAAACCAGCUCCCAUUUUAAUAGACAUUGCAAAAGCAGAAGGCCUGGACAAUGUCCUAACAGCUAUAAAUUCUGAAUAAAUAAAAUCUAACUAAUAGACAUUUUCUGCAUAGUUGUAAAUGCCAAUUCCUCAUUAAAACAAUCCAUUUAGACAUUUUUCCCCUAUGGUACAUUUUUAUUAUAAUAACCUAUAGGAUUAUUUGCUUGUAGUGUGCCAAUCUUUUGUGUUAAAAAUUAAAGGAUAGGUUUUUGCUUUAGAAAGUUUAGCAUUAGUGGAGUUUACUGUUACAAUAUUCCAGUCUUCUCAUUUUCUUUCAAGAUAACUGACACCCAAUUAGAUAAUGAAACUCAAAACUGUGUAAUUUUUUAUUCUAAAAAAUCUUCUUAGUCUUGAUCCCAACUGUCACAAACAAGAAGUUGUGGAAGUAAGGAAAAUACUAGUAAUCAAGGAACUGAGUGUUGGUGUAACAUCCCUUUAGCAUUUACCUGCACUCAAAUUGCUUUGUAUCAUGAGAUUUCCUAGAGAGAGAGAACGCUCAGUGAGAGUUCUCUUUCAGAUUUUUUCAGUUUUCUUUCAGAUUUAUUUUUUCAGGAUGAUAACAUAUUUAUGAAAUUAAAGCGCUAUUUUGAAGACAAAAGAUGGGGGAAAGAACAUCAAUAAUUUUUCAGACAAACCUGUCAUAAAGUCAUAUUGUCAUGUUUCUUUCAUUAUUACCAUGAAAUCUUGCUUCUUUUAAUAGAUUUUUUUCCUCUAUAUUUAUACUCUUUCUGCUUAGCUGCCACAGUAAAAUGAUUAUUGUUUUUGGGUAGUUUUGUAGCUUUCUCUUUUUUCUCUCACAUCCACUAUUUUGUUCUCUUCCUUACCCCUACCUACCCUCUCCCAAUGUGUCUAAAUGGCUCAGAGGGUCCUGAGACAUUUUGAUCUCCCUCCUAAAGGAAGCACUAUGCUCGUGCCUGGUACAUAGUAGAUGCUCAGUAAAUUUAUGCUGCAUAAAUUAAUGAAUUUGCAUAACAUUCAGUUCAUUGCUGUUGAGCAGUGGGUUCUCAAACUUUAUUGUGCAUUGCAAUGACCUGGAGCACAUGGUAAAACACGAAAUCCCAUGUCUCACCCCCAAAGUUUCUGAUUCAGCAGCUCUAGAGUGGAGCCUAAAAAUCUGCAUUUCUGGCCAGGUGAGGUUGCUCAGCCCUGUAAUCCCAGGACUUUGGGAGGCUGAGUGGGGAGGAUUGCUUGAGGCCAGGAGUUAGAGACCAGCCUGGGCAACAUAGCAGGACUCCAUCUCUACAAAAAAAAAUUUUUUUAAUUAGCCAAGUAUGGUGGUAUGUGCCUGCAGUCCCAGCUACAUGGGAGGCUGAGGUGGGAGGAUCCAUUGAGCCCUGGAGUUCAAGGUUGCAGUGAGCUAAUUGAUCUUACCACUACACUCCAGCCUGGGCAACGGAGUGAGACCCUGUCUCAAGAAAAAAAAAAGUCUGCAUUUCUAACAAGUUCCCAGUGAUGCUGAUGCUGCUGGUCUCAGGACCCAGCUUUGAGAACCACUGCCUAAAAGUCAAGGGCCAAAUAAAAAUAAUCAGAUUUGUUUUGGAGGUCUAUGCUCUUGCUUUGGAUUCAGUGGGUAAGCCAUCUGCCUGAAGAAUCCUCCCUCUAGGAUCUUUUGAUCCUACCUUUUUGAUGGUAACAUCACAUGUAUGAGGAAUUGAAAUAUAUUUGCACAUUUGAAAAUGUGUACAGAGAAAAAAUUCUACUCUGUUGACCCCACAGGUGAUUGGAAUGCCUUAGAAUCCCACCAUCUCGGCCACCAGCAACAUUUUUUCAACUACCUUUUAGCCUCUGAAGUAGCCCCUGAAUUCUAGGAGAAACUGUAUGAUAAACAUGAUCACUGCAGAUCUAUGGUUAGAAGCCAGACAUGCCCAGGUUCUUCCUGUUGACAGAUGCGCCUGACUUUCCACAUGACUUGUUCAGAAAGCUUCAGGCUAGGUCUAACCAAAGGCAAACGUACACUUGGUCAGGGAACAAAACCUAUCUGUCCACUGUUUUGCUUUAUGCCCACUAGUUUCUCAACAUUCUCCCUCUCCCCUCACACACACACAUACCACCACUCAAACUGCACCCCAACUCUAAUUGACUUCAGAAGGUGAUUUCCUCAGCCUGCCUUAUCUUUUCUUUAAAACCUUAGCUGUAUACAGGAAAGAAAGUAUUAUACUUCUGAAGGAUAAAUAGUAUACCUAGAACCAUUCUUAUUUUGAAAAUUGGGAAGCAUCCGUGUGUUGCCUUUGGAGUGACAGUAUUAAAGGGUUUGCAAAUUGCUGUUUUCCUUGGGAGGAUUACUCAAAAUUAAAAAGCAGAAAAGCUGAGUUUGGAAGAUUGCCCUUUCUUGAUUCCAUUCCAGCUUUGCUAGGUUUUUUUUAGCACGCUGUCAACACUUACUUGACUGUCCUUGCUCACUGGAAUUCCCAAAUAUUCCCUAUAAAAAUAUCAGACCACCAGCAAGAAGGGUGGGGAGUGAGAAAGGAAGGUUGCUAUCUCACCUGGGGAGAUAGCCGCCUGUCAUUUUCAACAAAACACCUGACCUUCAUCAUGGAUCCUCUUAUGUGCAAACAGAUAAAUUAGCUUGUGAAAUUAUAUUACUAAGAGGACAACUGCACUUAAAAAGGAUCAUAGAAGCUCUUUAAAUAGAAUAGUGUUUGUUUGUCAAUAAUAAAAUAUUUAUGGGAGGCCGGGCACAGUGGCUCACGCCUGUAAUCCCAGCACUUUGGGAGGCCGAGGCAGGAGGAUCGCUUGAGUCCAGGAGUUUGAGACCAGCCUGGGGCAACAUGGCAAAACCCUACCCCUACCAAAAAUAUGAAAAUUAGCCGGGCAUGGUGGCAUGCAGCUGUAGUCCCAGCUACUUGGGUGGCUGAGGCAGGAGAAUCGCUUGAACCUGAGAGGCAGAGGUUGCAGUGAGCCAAGAUAGUGCCACUGCACUUCAGCCUGGGCGACAGAGCAAGACUCUGUCUCAAAAAAAAAAAAAAAAAUUAUGGGAGGGGUAUAAAAGUUGAGGUGUAAUGAGUAUUCAUCAAGAAUUAAUAGGAAGCAAAUUUGAAAUUUGCUCACAGAGAAAUCACACCAGUAUAUCAAAAACAGCUAAUACUACACAAAAAACAUAAAUGCCAUAAAAACACUUUUAUUUAUUAUUUUAUAAGGUUACAUUUGUUUUCUGGGCAUACUCAGUUGAGGUAAAUGGUAGGAUUCAUUUGUAUCACCUGGACACAGCUCAGCUGUAUGGAGUGGUAAGUGUCCUGUUAUUUCUGUAACAACAACAAUGAGGAGAGCUGACGCUGACAUUUUUUCUUUCAGUGUAUUGGGAAAUCCUCAUUCUCGUGAAAACUGAAAAUUAACUGUGUUCAUGGGUGAAUAAAAUUAGGCUGCUUGAGAGGGA